AGAUCGGCAGCCUCAGCUGCUGCCGUAGCUGUCGGGAUCGUCCCCUGCGGGGCAGCAACAGCGGGGCUCCGACGGCUGAGGGGGGCGCCUUCUGCUUGCGCGCUCUGCGUCCCUCUCCGUGGUCUGCCCUUCGCCCCGCGACCCCGGCCGAGGGUGGGAGCAGCGCGGGGUCGCAUCGGCCCGAGGCUAGCGGGGCUCGCCGUUCCGCCCGCAGCCAUGGAGGCCGGGCCGCCGGGCAGCGCCAGGCCGGCGGAGCCGGGUCCUUGCCUGAGUGGUCAGCGCGGCGCGGACCACACGGCUUCCGCCUCCCUGCAGAGCGUGGCCGGGACCGAGCCCGGGCGCCACCCGCAAGCCGUGGCAGCUGUGUUGCCUGCCGGGGGGUGCGGGGAGAGGAUGGGGGUCCCCACCCCGAAGCAAUUCUGCCCCAUCCUGGAGAGGCCGCUCAUCAGCUACACCCUACAGGCCCUGGAGAGAGUAUGUUGGAUAAAGGACAUUGUUGUGGCAGUAACUGGAGAGAACAUGGAAGUAAUGAAAAGUAUUAUUCAGAAGUAUCAGCAUAAACGCAUCUCACUGGUCGAAGCUGGAGUGACCCGCCACAGGUCAAUUUUCAAUGGACUAAAAGCACUGGCAGAAGAUCAGAUCAACUCUAAACUCUCUAAGCCAGAAGUAGUGAUUAUCCAUGAUGCUGUGAGACCAUUUGUUGAGGAAGGUGUCCUUCUUAAAGUUGUCACAGCUGCUAAGGAACACGGGGCAGCAGGAGCCAUUCGACCUCUUGUAUCUACUGUCGUCAGUCCAUCUGCUGAUGGUUGCUUAGACUACUCGCUAGAACGUGCCAGACACAGAGCAAGUGAAAUGCCCCAAGCUUUUCUAUUUGAUGUGAUUUAUGAAGCAUAUCAGCAGUGUAGUGACUAUGACUUGGAAUUUGGAACUGAGUGUUUGCAAUUGGCCCUAAAAUACUGUUGCACUAAAGCCAAACUUGUAGAAGGAUCACCUGACCUCUGGAAGGUGACCUACAAACGAGAUCUCUAUGCGGCUGAAUCGAUUAUUAAGGAGAGAAUUUCCCAAGAGAUUUGUGUAGUUAUGGAUACAGAAGAAGAUAACAAACAUGUAGGUCAUCUUCUUGAAGAAGUGCUGAAAAGUGAAUUAAAUCAUGUAAAAGUCACAUCUGAGGCUCUGGGUCAUGCUGGCAGACAUCUUCAGCAAAUCAUCUUAGAUCAAUGCUACAAUUUUGUUUGUGUGAAUGUUACAACCUCUGAUUUUCAAGAAACCCAGAAGUUACUGAGCAUGCUUGAAGAGAGUAGUCUUUGCAUUUUAUAUCCUGUUGUUGUUGUUUCAGUUCAUUUUCUUGAUUUUAAAUUAGUACCUCCCAGUCAGAAAAUGGAAAACCUAAUGCAGAUUAGAGAAUUUGCAAAGGAAGUAAAAGAAAGAAAUAUUUUGUUAUAUGGGCUUCUCAUAUCUUACCCACAGGAUGAUCAGAAGCUACAGGAGAGUUUAAGGCAAGGUGCUAUCAUUAUUGCUUCAUUAAUCAAGGAAAGAAAUUCUGGACUCAUUGGUCAGCUUCUGAUAGCAUGAAGAACACAAAAAAUUACCUAUUUUCUAAAACAUCUAUUUGCGUAUCUUAAUUGUGCUUUGUGCCCCCGCUGCUGUGUGUGGUAGAAUGUUUCAGUUGUCUUUUAUAUCUUCUCUAUAAUUUGUAGGAUGUGAUGCUUAGAUUAUAAAGCAGAUUAAUGUUUAUAUCUGUGAAAUAAAGAAUACUUUUGUGUAUGACAAAUAUUAAUUGCCUGAACCAGAAAAAAAUAGUAGAUAAGUGGAAAAUAAUAGCCUUCAAAUGAAUCUUUCCACAGAGACAUGAACGGUCAAAUAGAAAUAAUGAUGGGGUGAGCUAUUCUUUCAAGGAAUGAGAAUUUAGAAAACUUCAGUUAUUAUCCUAACUGUUAAUUAAUAAUUUACACUAUUAUGAAGCUAAUGGAUAAACUUCAGAAUUAUUCUCACUUCUAUAAUUGUCCUGUCACCAGGUGAUAUUUUGUCUUUUUGUCUUGUGUUAAAAAUGUCUACACUUUAAUAAAAAAGGGUGAGUGGGAUACCAGGGAACGGAACUGUUUGUUUCUAGCAUUUUCCCCAUUUGCCACAUAUUACUCAAGAUCCCUAAAACAGAUGUCAUUUCCUUCUUUUCUGUUUUUAAAUUGUAUGUUAUUUUUGGUUUAUGAACUAUAAUUAUGACUUACAUUAUUUUAAAGGGUCUCUAGUUUUUCUGAAUGAACUUAAAAGUGUCUGGAAAGUUUCGUAGGUGAUUCUGGUCAAUCCCUGGUUAGUUAUCUUCUAUAAGGUAGAGAAUCUAUUGUACAUCAUAGAGUUAAAUUAGUUAUUUCAAUUCAGAUACUGCUACCUUUUAAAAUCAAGUUCUUAUUUCCAGUUUUCAUUGGUAUAUACAUCUGAAAUAUUAAUAUUUUCCCUUGCAUGUUAUAAUUAUGGGUGUCCUUUAAUUCAUUAGAGGUGACUUUUAAUCUAUACAUACACUUACUCUAUUUAUUUUAUUUUUUAUUGUUUUGAAAUGCAGUCGCCCUCUGUCAGGCUGGAGUGCAGUGGCACAAUCUCAGCUGACUGCAACCUCUGCCUCCUGGGUUUAAGCAAUUAUCCUCCCUCAGCCUCCCGAGUAGCUGGGAUUACAGGCACCUGCCACCACACCUGGCUAAUUUUUUUUUUUUUUUUUUUUUUUUGUAUUUUUAGUAGAGAAGGGUUUUCGCCAUGUAGGCCAGGCUGGUCUUGAACUCCUGACCUCAAGUGAUCUGCCUGCCUCGGCCUCCCAAAAUGCUGGGAUUAUAGGUGUGAGCCACCAUACCCAGCCAACAUACAUUUAUUUUAUUGAAACAGAUUAGGGCUUAGGCUGCACGUGGAAACUAUAAAAGUUGCAUGAAGUGUUUUCAGUUAAAGAUACACUAUACAAUAUCUACCUUGUGGAAUUUUUAUUUAACAUGUUGGGUGAUUUUCCCUCUAGUGUUCAAGUAUAUAUAUAGUAGGAGAGUUUAUAUUUUACAUUCUCCUAAUUGAAAUGUGUUAUUUGAAUGUAGGCUUGUAUCUAAAUUCCUGGGCCUGCCCUUUUUCUCUCUCUAGGAAUAUUAAGAAAUUUAAAAUCCAUUAAUUUAAGUUUUUGAGGAUGGAAAUAGGUAAGCAAUGUGUGGAUUGUGGUUAGGAAUGUCUGUGCCUUUGUUCAGAUGUCGGCUGUGUGUGUGACGAAAACCACAGCUGCCAAGUCCCCAACAUGCACCUGUUGAAGUCAUCAGGUGAAAAUGUUUAAGACUUUGAAAGUGCUCAUAAAGGAAGAAGGGGAAAUGUUAUCAAGGCUUUAAAGAGAGGGUAAGUGCCUUGAAGAAGAAUGCAGUAAACUGGGCAUAUUUGUGGCACAGCAAAAUCACCCUGAUCGCUGGAGUGCUGGCUGAGUUAACAUAGACUUCAGCUUAAGGAAUCCUACAGCAGACAAGAAUUUAUCUCAGAGUACUUACUAUGACAUUACCCUAGGCAACUGGUAACAUUUAGUAUAAUUUAGUUAAUAAAAUAUUAAGUUGUGCCUGGAAAAAAUAGCAUUUGGUCCUUCAUAGCAGGCAAAGCAAUUCACAGCAUUGGGAAAAAAAAAUACAUACAUACAUAUACAUGUAUGUAUACCCAUAUAUAUGUAUAUACAUGCAUGUAUACCCAUAUAUAUGUAUAUACUUACAUGUAUAUACAUAUAUAUGUAUGUACGUACAUAUAUACCCAUAUCUAUGUAUGUACGUACAUAUAUACCCGUAUAUAUGUACGUACAUAUAUACACAUAUAUGUAUGCACGUACAUAUAUACACAUAUAUGUAUGUACGUACAUAUAUACACAUUAUGUACAUACAUAUAUACGUAUAUAUGUACAUGCAUGUAUGUAUGUAUAUACGUACGCAUACACACAUAUAUUUAUAUACGUACGCAUACACACAUAUAUGUAUAUACGUACGCAUACACACAUAUAUGUAUAUACGUACGCAUACACACAUAUAUGUAUAUACGUACGCAUACACACAUAUAUGUAUAUACGUACGUAUAUACACACAUAUAUGUAUAUACGUACGUAUAUAUGUAUUUUUAUGUUUUAUGUAUAUGUAUUUUAUAUGUAUAUAUAUCUGCACAUCCUUCACUAUUUUCAUGAGGAAAUUGGAGCUCAGGGAUCUUAGUUACCUUGCCAAAAUCAUGUGACUGAAUAGUAACAAAAGUUUGGGCUUAAAAUAAGGAAGACUGAUAAUAAGUGUUAAGCUUAUAUUCCUGUCUAACAAUGACCCCUGGCAAAGACAUCUGAUAUAUAAGCCACGUCUGAUAUAUAAGACGUGAUAUAUAAGCCAGAGGCACUGAAUGAACAUUGGCGAAAUGGACAAGAAGGGUGGGACACUUAUGUCCAGGGACUAGGUGAAAGUCCUGGAGCUUUUGGCUUUCCAGCCACCUUCCCAGCAUAAAGAAAUUGUAGCUAAAGUUAAGGGAAUGAAUAGAAGUAUUGGCCAAAAGAGAAAUUAUUUUGUUGUUUAAGAGAUCUGGCCGGGCGCGAUGGCUCACGCCUGAAAUCCCAGCACUUUGGGAGGCCGAGGCAGGCAGAUUACGAGGUCAGGAGAUCCAGACCAUCCUGGCUAAUGCGGUGAAACCCCGUCUCUAGUAAAAAUACAAAAAAAAUAGCCAGGCAUCGUGGCGGGCGCCUGUAGUCCCAGCUACUCAGGAGGCUUAGGCAGGAGAAUGGCGUCAACCUGGGAGGCGGAGCUUGCAGUGAGCCGACAUAGCGCCACUGCACUCCAGCCUGGGCAACAGAGCAAGACUCCGUCUCAAAAAAAAAAAAAAAAAAAAAAAGAGAGAUCCAGAGGUAACUUUACAGUUACAUUUUCAUCACUGCUUCUGUAAAUUUACUUUAGUAAAAGCUGUCUAUUCUCACUUUAUUUUCCAAAAUCUCUUAAAAAAUAAUAGUGAUUAUGCUUCAAGGUUUCUGAAAAUGCUUCCACUUGUGGGAAAUUUUGUUGCAAAAUGGUUUUCUUUCUAAACUUACGCUAGUUAGUUAAAUGCAAAUUAAAGUUAGUCGUCUUAGGAGUUCAUCAUAGCGUGAGUAAUGGUUUGAUUAAUGACAUUUUGGUAGAGGUCCUAUUUUUUUUCAUAAAAGUGCUCAAUUUGAGAUGACUUGUUGCAAGUAUACUCAUUUACAGGUAAGAGUCAGCUCCCUAUAUUCUCUCAGAGUCAUUGUUAUGGUUAUUAUUGUAAGUAUUUUACAUUAAUUUAACAGAAAUUUUUUCUUCCCUAACUUAUAACUCAACUUUAUGUAAAUACAGUGAUCAUCUUAUAAAAAUCAAAUUACAGAAUGUCUUAAAAUCUGUAAAUUUGACUUUGUUUUAAUGUUGAAACUACAAAUUCACAGAGGCAUAAAUCUAACAUCUUAAUUAAAAUGUCAACCAUAUGCAAGAAGAAAGAUAGAAGUUAUUUAGAAAGUUUAAUUUGAAAACAGAAUAAUGAAGCAUUUUAAUUGAUAUAGGAUUUGUUAGUAUGGCUUAAAAUCAGUGGACUAGAAGUAGCUGUGUAGGUGGUGGUUGGCAUUAUAGUUGCAUUUAUAUAUGUUCUUAUUAAUUUCAGUUUCAAAAUUGUAAGAAGCAUAUGCAUAUUUUUAAGGUGACAUUGAAAAGUACUAUAAAGAUUCUAAAUAUGUUGUUUUUACAAAACAAAAUGUAAAUAAAUUAUUGAUUUAAAAUCUAA